AAUUCAAGUCAUGCAGGCUGUGAGAAACGCGGGGUCGCGGUUCCUGCGGUCCUGGACUUGGCCCCAGACAGCCGGCAGGGUCGUGGCCAGAACGCCGGCCGGGACCAUCUGCACAGGCGCUCGACAGCUCCAAGACGCUGCGGCCAAGCAGAAAGUUGAACAGAACGCGGCUCCCAGCCACACCAAGUUCAGGUGAGCCCCACUUGGACCAGCCCUCUGGAGACCCGCAACCCCUGACUCUUGCCCGACACCCUCCAGAGUCAGAACCAGUGAAUUUUCAGCUAUGUCACUUGCUAUCCGUGGGACCUUAUGCAAAUAAAUCUGAGCCUCAGCCUUCUCAUCUAAAAAUGCGGAUAAUGCUGAGAGAGGUUGUGAGAAUCAGAUGAGCCGUGGUACAGAGUAAAUGUUCAGUGAACAUUCGUUAAAUCAAUGAGUGAAUGUGAGAUAUCCAUAACAUGUAUCAGCGUUCUUUUCUUCUGAGAUGGAGAUCUUUUCAGACCAAUAACCUUCCCUGCCUCCAAAACAAAAUGGGGAGGUAGAGGGCGCUAGCGAUGGAACAGAUGUUCCUGCACGUCUUACGGAUGGUCCAGGGUGGGUUUUGUGCUCAGCCCUAGGAACUGGCAUCUUGCUUCCCACCAGUGCCACCACCUCUGUAUGCUGUAUACACAUCCACUUAACUUCACAUCCAUUUAACAAACAUUUACCAAGAAUCUACUAUGAGUGAGACACCAUGCUAGGUGCCGUGAAUACAGAUACAAAAGAUCAUUCCUCCCCACAAGUAGUUCACAGUCUUUGAGGGAAGACAAACAUGCAAACAUUUUAACCAUAAUCUGCUCAAUAAUAUAAUGGAGGUAAGCAUUGGUUGGAAGUAUGAAAUCAUAAGUGUCUAACUCCUGGCCGGGUGCAGUAGCUCAUGCCUUUAAUCCCAGCACUUUAGGCGGCCAAGGUGGGCGAAUUACUUGAGGUCAGGAGAUCGAGACCAGCCUGGCCAACAUGGCGAAACCCCGUCUCCACUAAAAGCACAAAAACUAGCCAGGCGUGAUGUCUGGCACCUGUAAUCCCAGCCACUCAGGAGGCUGAAGUAGAAGAAUCGCAUGAACCCAGGGAGCGGAGGUUGCAGUGAGCCAAGAUCACGCCACUGUACUCCAGCCUGGGUGACAGAUUGAGACUCUGUCUCAAAGAAAAAAAAAAAAAAAAAGAAUAAGUGUCUCAUUCCUGAGGAAAUCAGGCAAGACCAUGGAGAAAAGAACAUGGAGCUCAGAAGUGAAUGGGAGUUCAUCUGGACAAGUUGAAGUGGGUCAUUGGAGACAAAGCAUUUACCCUCCCAUUCCAGGAGAGGAGAGCUCUCUGAGGUGGGCAGGAAAGAAAUUUGAGGAGAUCCCAAUUGCACACAUUAAAGCAUCCCACAACAACACACAGAUCCAGGUAGUCUCUGCUAGUAAUGAGCCCCUUGCCUUUGCUUCCUGUGGCACAGAGGGAUUUCGGAAUGCCAAGAAGGGCACAGGCAUCGCAGCACAGACAGCAGGCAUAGCCGCAGCGGCGAGAGCUAAACAAAAGGGCGUGAUCCACAUCCGAGUUGUGGUGAAAGGCCUGGGGCCAGGACGCUUGUCUGCCAUGCACGGACUGAUCAUGGGCGGCCUGGAAGUGAUCUCAAUCACAGACAACACCCCAAUCCCACACAACGGCUGCCGCCCCAGGAAGGCUCGGAAGCUGUGAUGGGAAGGAGGCCUGCACUUGGACCUGACCUCAAGCCUCAGCUCCAGUGGGACCUUGUAAAAUGCUCCCUGUCAGAGCUCUCCAGAAUAUGCUUGUUGGAGAUCCUUCAGGCAGUAAGGGAGAGUUUUGCCUCCUUACACAGUGGCCUUUGCUUGCACCUCCAGCUGGAGAUGGGUGUGCCCCAGAAGUAAGCUUUGCAUCUCUUACAAGAGGGGAGCUACAGGGGCAGCCGUGGCCUAGGCCCAAACUCUGCUCUGAGAAAAUAAAUAUCUGUACCACCUGUCAUAAUUUUGAGAUUUUUUGCUUUCAGAGUUACGUAAUUCCUAAUUCCUCUUGAAAAAGAGAGUGUGAAAUGAGGUGAGGCCUCAGAUGAAAGUAAAAUAUAAAUGUGAGUUGCUAUUUACCAGACACUUCUGGUUUCAGAUAUUUCUUUUCUAGCCCCUUACCCAAGAUUUCUAGAGCUAAUCCUAGUAACUUUUCUUAUUAAUGACUUAUAAUUUGGCCCCAAAUUGGAGCUUUUUGCCACCUACCUCUGGAUUCUGAUGGAUUUCGCCAUUAUGGGCAUGUUUAAAGUUAGCCCUAAACACAGGAUUUUCUACAAGUGGACAGUCAAACUCCCCACACUAAAGUGGCAGUCAUCGUUUACACUCCAUGGGCUUCAGCAGUCCCAGCACUAACGAGAGAGUGCCCUAAAAGCGGGGAGGGUAGAGUUGUACAAAACAUGAUUCUUGGCCAGGCACGGUGGCUCACACCUGUAACCCUGGCACUUUGGGAGGCCAAGGCGGGUGGAUCACUUGAGUCCAGUUAGAGACCAGCCUGGGCAACAUGGUGAAACCCCCUCUCUACUAAAAAUACAAAAAUUAACCAGGCAUGGUGGUGUGCGCCUGUAAUCCCAGCUACUCUGGAGGCUGAGGCAUGAAAAUCGCUUGAACCCAGGAGGUGGAGGCUGCAGUGAGCUGAGAUCAUCCUACUGCACUCCAGCCCAGGUGACAGCGAGACUGUCUCAAAAAAAUAAAUAAAUAUAAAUAAAAAUUUAAAAAAAUUAAAAAAAAAAACCUGAUGAUUCUCUAGAAAAUAGGGUGGAUGGCAGGAUGGGCUUGAGUAGAGUCCAAAUCUAGAAGUGCAGAAAGCAAGUUGAUAAGGAACCUGGGUAGUGCUGGCAGUGGGGCACAACUCAGGACCCCCAGGCAGGACUGACUGCUCCUCUGUUGGGGCUCUAGGGUUCCUGGAUACGGCACAGAGGCCAAAGGUGGGGGCUCUAGAGACACGACCAGAGAGUCCCCUCUUCCACAGGCAAAGACUAAGGGUGAGAGUAUCACCAGAAGCUGAGAAGGAGUGGUCAAGUACACAAAAGCACUGUUCCUCCCAGAUGAGUGCAGGAAGGGCUGCUGACCAGAAGGGGAAGGCACUGUGGAGUUUUACUUCUGUGUCCAGCCAGCUAAGUACUGUGAUCUGCCUGAACUCAGUAUAGGAAAAGACACAGAUGCCCCCUUAAAUAGGCAAGAGGCUGUGUUAGGACAAAGAAAGGAGGAAGAUCACGAACCAAGACAUGAAUUUAGAGGAAAAAUGCCUCCCUACUGCCUUCUCUUUAGUCCUUAGCAGGUCCUAUGAAGGCCAUCUUGUGACAGUGACCAAAGAAGCCCAACCGGAGGCUUCUUGGAUCAAAGCCACUGUCGGAAGGAAUUAGACUGUUUCACCGCAAAACUACAUAUAAACACAAUGCAUUAAAACAUGGUGCACUUGAAAAUUGCACUUCGCGAUUUGAUAUGGUUUGGUGGACAGAGGGCCCGUAGCCAUCAGACAGUUCAAUCAGGGUCUGAGCAGGAAACAGCUCACAAGGUUUAAGAGAAAAGCUCAAUGAAAGCUCUUUGCAGAGGCAUGGGUAAGAUUAAGGAAAUAAAGAAGGUGGACUACAAAGCAGCUGCCACCCUAGGCUAGAAGAGGCAGGGAAGAACAGUUCCUAGAACCUGGCAGGAGCUGCCACAGCAGCAGAGUGCACCUCUGCCAAAACCAUGGCCUGAGGGAGAGGGAAGAAAUGCCUGGCUGUUCCCGGCCUGUAGUCCCUUGCUGGGGUCCCCCUUGGCUGAUCCCAAAAGGAAGCAAAAAGGAAGGGAACUCAGUGUUGUGGUACUUGGAGGCUCAGCCUCCCAGGCUGCAGAGUGGAUCUGGAGGGGCACGUAGAGGAUAGUAAACACAGGAGGCUUCUGUGGCUUCUGUAAGUCCUCCAUACACCAUAGGUUUUUAUUUUGGUUUUGGUUUUUGAGUCUCGUUGUCACCCAGGCUGGAUUGCAGUGGUACGACCAUGGUUCACUGCAGCCUCAAACUCCUGGGCUCAAGUGAUCCUCCAGCUUCAGCCUCCUGUGAGCAUCUGGGACUACAGGCGCAUGCCACCACACAUGGAUAAUUUUUGUAUUUUUUGUAUUGAGACCAGGUCUUGAACUCCUGGUCUCAAGCAGUCCCCCCACCUCGGCCUCCCAAAGUGCUGGGAUAACAGGCGUGAGCCACUGCGCCUGAUCCACACACCAUAGUUUUUAAAAUGUUAUUUUACUCACAAGAGGGCUUUGGAAAGGAAGAUCCUGCCCAGCAGAGCCUACAUGCGCAGACAGGACAGAGGACCCUUAAGGAUCAAUGGUCUUGUUGCCGGAAAUGGAUGUCUGGCGCAACCCCCGGAGCUAGUUUUGGGGAGGCCGCCUUGUUGACUGUGCACUGGAAAAUGCACAUUGCUUUAUCGUGAGCUCUCGGUGCACAGUGUGGUUUCCAGGCUCUGAGUGGCCAAUAAAGCUGGUGCUGUCUUAAA